GCUUGCUGGGAAGAGAGGCGAAGCCAGGUCACCUUUCAAGGACCCAGAAGUAGGGUUUUGGCCUAGGUAACGGGGCAGAGAUGUGGUUCGAGAUUCUCCCCGGACUCUCCGUCAUGGGCGUGUGCUUGUUGAUUCCAGGACUGGCUACUGCGUACAUCCACAGGUUCACUAACGGGGGCAAGGAAAAAAGGGUUGCUCAUUUUGGGUAUCACUGGAGUCUGAUGGAAAGAGAUAGGCGCAUCUCUGGAGUUGAUCGUUACUAUGUGUCAAAGGGUUUGGAGAACAUUGAUUAAGGAAGCAUUUUCCUGAUUGAUGAAAAAAAUAACUCAGUUAUGGCCAUCUACCCCUGCUAGAAGGUUACAGUGUAUUAUGUAGCAUGCAAUGUGUUAUGUAGUGCUUAAUAAAAAUAAAAUGAAAAAAA